UUCUAAUGAUCCCAUCACCAAAGUAGCAAACGUAGUACCCAGGAUUUUUUUUUUCCUAGUUAGUCUUCAUGUUAAGUACAAUCUUACCUCAAAAUUGUUAAUGUCUGUGGUUUAAAAAAAAACAUGAAUCAGAAAUGGUGUGGGUAGUUUAGAAAAUGAGUUAGGUUCAGGUGGCCGGUUAGCUCAGUUGGUCAGAAAAUGAGUUAGGUUCAUCUGGGAAGACUUCCUGGGAGAAAAGACCCUGGGUUCUGAGGUAAAGUGGAGUAGGGAUAAGAUGUGCAAGGCAGGAAGGGAGUUGAUUCCUUAGGUAAGUGAAUUAUUGGAGGUGAGGGGUAUGUCUGGCUCCUGAGUCAGCCACGAUGUGCCUCCUUGUCUUCCCCCUUGUCCCCAGGAGUCCAGAUUACAUCCUACCCUGCAGUCCUGGAUGGCGCCUCCGACUUGCAGCUUCCUUCCUGCUUUCCGUCUUCCCGCUGCUAGACCUUCUUCCAGUUGCUUUGCCACCAGGGGCAGGCCCAGGACCCAUAGGGCUAGAGGUGUUGGCAGGGUGCGUGGCAGCUGUGGCCUGGAUCAGCCACAGCCUGGCCCUGUGGGUGUUGGCACAUUCCCCUCAUGGCCACUCCCGGGGUCCCUUGGCCUUGGCCCUGGUAGCCUUGCUGCCAGCUCCAGCCCUAGUGCUGACCGUGUUGUGGCAUUGCCAGCGAGGCACACUUCUGCCCCCACUUCUCCCAGGGCCCAUGGCCCGCCUAUGCUUGCUCAUCCUGCAGCUGGCUGCACUCUUGGCCUAUGCACUGGGAUGGGCAGCUCCUGGGGGACCACGAGAACCCUGGGCUCAGGAGCCCCUCCUGCCCGAGGAUCAAGAACCUGAGGUGGCUGAAGAUGGGGAGAGUUGGCUGUCACGCUUUUCCUAUGCCUGGCUGGCACCCUUGCUGGCCCGUGGGGCCUGUGGAGAGCUCCGGCAGCCUCAGGACAUUUGCCGCCUCCCCCACAGACUGCAGCCAACCUACCUGGCUCGUGUCUUCCAGGCACACUGGCAGGAGGGGGCACGGCUGUGGAGGGCCUUGUAUGGGGCCUUUGGACGGUGCUAUCUGGCACUUGGACUGCUGAAGCUGGUGGGGACCAUGUUGGGAUUCUCAGGGCCCCUGUUGCUCUCCCUACUGGUGGGCUUCCUGGAAGAGGGGCAGGAGCCACUAAGCCACGGCCUGCUCUAUGCUCUGGGGCUAGCCGGUGGGGCUGUGCUGGGUGCUGUGCUGCAGAAUCAGUAUGGGUAUGAGGUAUAUAAGGUAACACUUCAGGCACGGGGGGCUGUGCUGAACAUCCUGUACUGCAAGGCUUUACAGCUGGGGCCCAGCCGCCCUCCUACUGGGGAGGCCCUGAACCUACUAGGCACUGACUCUGAACGGCUGCUUAACUUUGCUGGGAGCUUCCAUGAAGCCUGGGGCCUGCCCCUGCAACUGGCCAUCACCCUCUACCUGCUGUACCAGCAGGUAGGCGUGGCCUUCGUGGGUGGUCUCAUCUUGGCACUGCUGCUGGUACCCGUCAACAAAGUGAUUGCCACCCGCAUCAUGGCCAGCAACCAGGAAAUGCUACAGCACAAGGAUGCGCGGGUUAAGCUUGUGACAGAGCUGCUGAGUGGCAUUCGGGUCAUCAAGUUCUGCGGGUGGGAGCAGGCACUGGGAGCCCGAGUAGAGGCCUGCCGGGCUCGAGAGCUGGGGCGACUCCGGGUCAUCAAAUACCUGGAUGCGGCCUGUGUAUACCUGUGGGCUGCCCUACCGGUUGUCAUCUCCAUCGUUAUCUUCAUCACCUAUGUCCUCAUGGGGCACCAGCUCACUGCCACCAAGGUGUUCACGGCCCUGGCACUGGUGCGAAUGCUCAUUCUUCCUCUCAACAACUUCCCUUGGGUGAUCAAUGGUCUCCUGGAGGCCAAAGUGUCCUUGGACCGGAUCCAGCUUUUCCUCGACCUUCCAAACCACAACCCCCAGGCCUACUACAGCCCAGAUUGUGGUAGAUUAGGAGCCCAAAUCAAGUGGCUUCUCUGUUCAGAUCCCCCUGCAGAGCCAUCUACAGUAUUGGAGCUGCAUGGAGCCUUGUUCUCCUGGGACCCAGUUGGAACCAGCCUGGAGACCUUCAUCAGUCAUCUCGAAGUGAAAAAGGGUAUGCUGGUGGGCAUCGUGGGGAAGGUCGGCUGUGGGAAGAGCUCCCUGCUGGCUGCCAUCGCUGGAGAGCUCCACAGGCUGCGUGGGCAUGUGGCAGUGCGGGGGCUGUCCAAGGGCUUUGGCCUGGCCACCCAGGAACCCUGGAUCCAGUUUGCCACCAUCCGAGACAACAUCCUCUUUGGGAAGACAUUUGAUGCACAGCUGUACAAGGAGGUGCUAGAAGCCUGCGCCCUCAAUGAUGACCUCAGUAUCCUGCCUGCUGGAGACCAGACAGAGGUGGGGGAGAAGGGUGUCACCCUUAGCGGAGGACAGCGUGCCCGGAUUGCCCUUGCUCGUGCUGUCUACCAGGAAAAGGAGCUCUAUCUCCUCGAUGACCCUCUGGCCGCUGUGGAUGCAGAUGUGGCCAACCACCUGCUGCACAGGUGCAUCCUGGGCAUGCUGAGCUACACCACACGGCUGCUCUGCACCCACCGCACUGAGUACCUGGAGAGGGCUGACGCGGUGCUGCUGAUGGAGGCCGGGCGCCUCAUCCGGGCUGGACCUCCCUCUGAGAUUCUGCCACUGGUACAAGCUGUCCCCAAAGCCUGGGCUGAGAAUGGACAAGAGUCUGACUCAGCCACAGCCCAGUCAGUACAGAACCCAGAGAAAACAAAGGAGGGGCUGGAGGAGGAGCAGAGCACAUCUGGUCGCCUGCUGCAGGAAGAAAGCAAGAAGGAGGGCGCCGUGGCCUUGCACGUGUACCAAGCUUACUGGAAGGCCGUGGGCCAGGGCUUGGCCUUAGCCAUCCUCUUCUCUCUGCUUCUCAUGCAAGCCACGCGGAACGCUGCUGACUGGUGGCUCUCCCACUGGAUCUCUCAGCUGAAGGCUGAGAAUAGCUCCCAGGAGGCGCAACCCUCCACCAGCCCAGCUUCUAUGGGGCUCUUCUCUCCGCAGCUGCUCCUCUUUUCCCCUGGAAACCUCUACAUCCCAGUGUUCCCACUGCCCAAAGCUGCCCCCAAUGGCUCCUCAGACAUCCGUUUCUACCUCACCGUGUAUGCGACCAUUGCUGGUGUAAAUUCCCUCUGCACCCUUCUCCGGGCAGUGCUCUUUGCAGCAGGCACCCUUCAAGCAGCUGCCACUCUGCAUCGCCGCCUGCUGCAUCGAGUCCUUAUGGCACCAGUGACUUUCUUCAAUGCCACACCCACGGGCCGGAUCCUAAACCGCUUCUCCUCUGAUGUGGCCUGUGCGGAUGACAGCCUGCCCUUCAUCCUCAACAUCCUCCUGGCCAACGCGGCAGGCCUGCUGGGGCUCCUGGCCGUGCUGGGCUCUGGCCUGCCCUGGCUGCUGCUCCUGCUGCCGCCUUUGAGCAUCAUGUACUAUCACGUGCAGCGCCACUACAGGGCCUCCUCACGGGAGCUGCGGCGCCUGGGCAGCCUCACCCUGUCUCCACUGUAUAGCCAUCUGGCCGAUACCUUGGCUGGCCUCUCUGUGCUCCGGGCCACAGGGGCCACCUACAGGUUUGAGGAGGAGAACCUGCGACUCCUUGAGCUAAACCAGAGGUGCCAGUUUGCCACCAGUGCCACAAUGCAGUGGCUGGACAUUCGGCUACAGCUCAUGGGGGCGGCAGUGGUCAGCGCUAUCGCAGGCAUCGCUCUGGUGCAGCACCAGCAGGGCCUCGCUAACCCAGGGCUGGUGGGCUUGUCGCUGUCUUAUGCCCUGUCCCUGACGGGCCUGCUCUCGGGCCUGGUGAGCAGCUUCACACAGACAGAGGCCAUGCUGGUGAGCGUCGAGCGGCUGGAAGAGUACACCUGUGACCUGCCCCAGGAACCCCAGGGCCAGCCACUGCAGCUGGGCACCGGCUGGCUGACCCAGGGGGGCGUGGAGUUCCAGGACGUGGUGUUGGCGUACCGGCCAGGGCUGCCGAAUGCCCUGGAUGGAGUGACCUUCUGCGUGCAGCCUGGAGAGAAGUUGGGCAUCGUGGGCCGCACAGGCUCCGGCAAGUCUUCCCUGUUGUUGGUGCUCUUCCGGCUGCUAGAGCCCAGUUCAGGGCGAGUGCUGCUGGACGGCGUGGACACCAGCCAGCUGGAGCUGGCCCAGCUCAGAUCCCAGUUGGCUAUCAUCCCCCAGGAGCCCUUUUUGUUCAGUGGGACUGUUCGGGAAAACCUGGACCCCCAGGGCCUACAUAAGGACAGGGCCUUGUGGCAGGCCCUGAAGCAGUGCCACCUGAGUGAGGUGAUUACAUCCAUGGGUGGUCUGGAUGGUGAGCUGGGUGAGGGGGGCCGGAGCUUAUCUCUUGGGCAGAGGCAGCUGUUGUGUUUGGCCAGGGCUCUCCUCACAGAUGCCAAGAUCCUGUGUAUCGAUGAGGCCACAGCAAGUGUGGACCAGAAGACAGACCAGCUGCUCCAGCAGACCAUCUGCAAACGCUUUGCCAACAAGACAGUGCUGACCAUUGCCCAUAGGCUCAACACGAUCCUGAACUCAGACCGGGUGCUGGUGCUACAAGCGGGGAGAGUGGUAGAGCUGGACUCCCCGGCCACCCUGCGCAACCAGCCCCACUCCCUGUUCCAGCAGCUGCUGCAGAGCAGCCAGCAGGGAGUCCCUGCCUCACUCGGAGGUCCCUGAGCCCAAUCCCACACCCUGCAGAGUUCUCCCCUCUCUCUGAUCCAGGCCGGGCCUAUACAGAGGUGCUGGCUGCUUGUUUACAUUCUCCUCUGGGGCUCUACCUCUCCACACUUCCCCAGAAGGGAAAAGGGCACCCUGGAUUACUCUUUGGAAAUCACUCCUUGGUGGGCAGCAUCCUGAGGCUUCCCCAGAACCAGGCCUCUGCUCUGGCCCUCUUGCAUCUGGAACGCCAGGUGGGUUUUUCUGGCAUAGGAGCCCACUUGCAUUUUCAUAGUUUUAUUUGAUAAAAUUCCAUCUUACAUUCUGUGUAUUAAAAAAAUAAUAUUUCUGGUGUGA